AAGCUGAGCCCAGGGAGGCUUUGAGGUACACAGGGUCCCUUGGGGGGCCUGAGAGCAGCCAUGAGGAGGCACAGUGAGACAGAUGUGGAAGAGCAGACCCAGGAGCUGAAGACCAUCACUCAGCUCCAGGAGCAGUGUCGGGCACUCCAGAUCCAAGGGGUGAAAGAGAAUAUGGACCAGAACAAGGCCACGCUGGCCCUCCUGCGCAGCAACAUCCGCCGCGGGGCCCAGGACUGGGCUUUGGCCAAGAAGUAUGACCAGUGGACCAUCUCCAAGGCCUGCGGGAAAAACUUGCCUUUGCGACUGGCGCACUGCCGCAGCACCAUGGAGGUGGUGCGGGAGAAGCUGCGCAAGUACGUCUUCGACCGCGUGAACAUGCACAACCUACUGAUCCACCUGGUGCGGCGGCGCGGGCAGAAGCUGGAGAGCAUGCAGCUGGAGCUGGACAGCCUGCGGAGCCAGCCCGACGCCAGCAAGGAGGAGCUGCGGCUGCUGCAGAUCAUCCGCCAGCUGGAGAACAACAUCGAGAAGACAAUGAUCAAGAUCAUCACCAGCCAGAACAUCCACCUGCUGUAUUUGGACCUGCUGGAUUAUCUGAAGACAGUGCUGGCAGGAUACCCCAUUGAGCUGGACAAGCUGCAGAACCUCGUGGUCAACUACUGCUCAGAGCUGUCGGAUAUGAAGAUCAUGUCCCAAGAUGCCAUGAUGAUCACGGAUGAGGUCAAGAGGAACAUGAGGCAAAGGGAGGCGUCCUUCAUCGAGGAGCGCCGGGCAAGGGAGAACCGGCUCAACCAGCAGAAGAAGCUGAUCGACAAGAUCCACACGAAGGAGACCAGCGAGAAGUACCGCCGGGGCCAGAUGGACUUGGACUUCCCCUCGAACCUGAUGAGCACGGAGACCCUGAAAUUGAGGAGAAAAGAGACCUCCACAGCAGAAAUGGAAUACCAGUCGGGCGUGACUGCUGUGGUGGAGAAGGUCAAGAGUGCUGUACGGUGCUCUCACGUCUGGGACAUCACUAGCCGCUUCCUGGCCCAGAGGAACACGGAGGAGAACCUGGAGCUGCAGAUGGAGGACUGUGAGGAGUGGCGGGUGCAGCUGAAGGCCCUGGUGAAGCAGCUGGAGCUGGAGGAGGCCGUGCUCAAGUUCCGCCAGAAGCCUAGCUCCAUCAGCUUCAAGUCCGUUGAGAAGAAAAUGACAGACAUGCUAAAAGAGGAAGAAGAGAGGCUCCAGCUGGCGCACAGCAACAUGACCAAGGGCCAGGAGCUGCUGCUGACCAUCCAGAUGGGCAUCGACAACCUCUAUGUCCGGCUGAUGGGCAUUAACUUGCCUGCGACCCAGAGAGAAGUGGUGCUCUCCAACACCCUCGAUUUGAACAGCAAGCUGGCGUACUGCGAGGGGAAGCUCACGUACCUGGCUGACAGAGUGCAGAUGGUGUCCAGGACCGAGGAGGGCGACACAAAGGUGAGGGACACCCUGGAGUCCUCGACUCUGAUGGAGAAGUACAACACCAGGAUCAGCUUUGAGAACCGGGAGGAGGAUAUGAUCGACACCUUCCAGUUCCCCGACAUGGACCACAGCUACGUCCCUUCGCGCGCCGAGAUCAAGAGGCAGGCGCAGCGGCUAAUCGAGGGGAAGCUCAAGGCGGCCAAGAAAAAGAAGAAGUAGCCCCGCCGCCCCGCUCCCUGCUUUGCUACACAAAUAAACAUUUUUCCAGGA